AGACUGCUAAUGCAAAAACUUUUAAGCUGUUCAUCCUUUUUUAAUGAAAAAGAUAAUAAGAUCAAUAAAAGCACCAUUCUUUACCACUUACUUAGAAUGAAUUUUUAUUUGUUCAAUGUAAGAGAGAUUGGCUAUUUCAAUGUGUUUCAAUAUUGGUAUAAGCUUUAAAUGACAAAGAUUUGUGUUUUAUGACUUACCUAUACAUCAACAGCACUGAAUUUUCUCAAAACUUAUUUAGGCAGCAUGACUUGGAAGGAAAAUAUUAACUAUUGAAUCACACUGAUGCUCUCUGGUCUAGUUAAGAUAGUUUUUUAGAUACUCCAUAUAAGCCUGGGUUUUGCUGACAAAAUUCACCUACAAAGCCCAGAGAGACUUACAGUCACUUGCAGGCAUUUCUUUAUAUUAAGGCCUUUAAAAAUAAAAUAUACAAGAUUCUGACAACACUUGCCUUAAUUGCUUAAGAACUUAAAAUAAGCUUGUUGGUAGAAAUGGUUUGCCAACUAGGGCAGUUUUGAGUCACCUUAUCCAGUCCCCGGAAUAUUGGAGUCUUGUAAAUAAUUAACAUUUGGGCAGUGGCUGAAAUAUUUCUGACCAGAGCAGUAGGCAUAAAGUUAUUAAGCAAGCUAUGCUGAAUACAAUGUGGAGUGAAACAGACUAAGAUUUGUACUGAGGCUGUAGAAUUUUCAGGCUGCCUACCUUGGGUGAGUGAUAGCAGUUUACUGAGACUGAGCCUCAGGAGAUAUAUAUGUACAUACAUAAGCACGUGUGUUUGUGUGUGUGUAUUUUCUGCCUUGUUAUAUAAUCCAUCAUUUGAUAAAAAGAGUCCCUGAAGUUUUAGAGAUACAUGUGGCAUUUGGCGGAGAAGAAACAUAACUAUACUUCAUAUGAGACAGUCAUUUUAGGCUUCAGUAUUGUAAUAAAAACUUACAUGAAGUAACACUUAAGAAAUAUUCUGAAAUCCUAAAAUGAAUAUAUUGUUCCAAGUUGCAGGGGGAUAAAACCUCAAUUUUAGAAAAUAUUAUUCAAGUAAUUGUUAUUGAGUCAAUUUCAUAAUUUAUCAAUAUGUGUUUAUAAAGUACAUGCAAGUAGAUUGUAAUAUGCCUUACUUUAGAGAUAUAAUUAUAUAUAUAUAGCUACUUUGUUAAUAGGAGACAUUUUUCUCAUGAAAAAAUAUAAAUCCCUCCUCAGAUUCAAACUCAAACUUAAAACACAUAAAUUCUAAAUUGCUGGAUUACUUAAGGUGUUUAGGUAAAGUAAGAGCAAACUAAUCAGUAAUAAAAUAUUGGCAAGUCCCCGUUUGUGGCUUUUUUCUAAAUCUUUCAUAAAUAUAGACAUUGUUCAAAUAUACUUAGAAAUAUAGAGUCUUGAGCUAUGUAUUUUAUUGUUAAGAAAAAAGAAUUUCCCUCUUGAAAAUUCCAUUUUAUUGCCCAUCAUUAAAUUUUACAUGACCCUAUGAACUUUUCAGAAUUGCAAAUUACUUAAGCAGUGUAAACUCAUAUUACUCAUAUACGUAUGUCUCUUUCAUUAAAAUGAUUAGAUUUAUAAAUUGAAAAUAUUAUCGUAACUAAUUGGCCUAAAACAUGAGGUUUAAUAAAAUGCAGAUUUUAAUCAGGAGCUUAAGAAUUUAGCCUAUGCUUUCUACUAUGUUUUUCUCACUUUCAAUGCCUUUUUUUCUUGUUUUCACAUCUACAUAGGGAAAUAAUCAGUAAAUUAUGAAAUAUUUUGAAAAAGACAUAAUUUAAAUAUUUACUAAUAAUAACUUUGUGCCUAUGUUUAAUAUUAUGCCAUGGAUAUAGCUGCCAUUCAAUACAUAGUUGUUGAAUAAACUAAUCAAAUUUAUUAUCCUUUUUUGUUGUUUGUGACUUGAUAAUACAACAGAUUGAAGAAUACAAUCAAACUGGUGCGGAAAUAUCAAGAUAAGUAAACCACAACCUCAGUCCUCAGAGAGAGUAAUUUUUACUAGGGGUUAUCCAAAAUCAUCUGAAGAUAUGUUUUCCUGAUCUGACAUAGUUCUUCAGAAGUGAAUAUGAAUAUAUAUUAUCCUGUUGAUUUAAAAAAUUCCAGUGAACACAGAAAACAUGUGUCAUCUAUUUUAUGUGAAUUAAAACCAAAAGAUCUAGGCAUGAAAUCAAAAACAUCAAGACAUCUCAUUCAAAAAGGUCAGGAGUCUGAAGAUGAAAUUGUGGAUGAAAAAUUGGAUACCAGUUUUAGGAUAUCAGUUUUCAAACUACCCAUAUACACUUCAGGUUCAUUGAAGAAUAAUGCAGUAUUGAGAGAGAAAAAACAACAUUUUUUUCCUGCAUAUCCUCAGCCAAUCUAUACUACUCAUCCAAAGCCAAUCAUUAAAAAAGACAUACGAUUGGAGCGGAGUAUGAAAGAGUUUUUUGCACCACAAAGAGCUGGUAUGAAACUCCGAACAUUUAGUGAUAUUGACAAAUAUUACACAGAACAAAAGAAGCAGGAAUACCAUAAAGAAAAAGUAAGAGUUGUAGCCAUGGCACAAGUUGCUCGAGAAAGAGUUAGAGUAGCUGUUAAUGAACAUUUGAAUCAGAAAAAAUAUGCUACACAAAAACUAAUUGAAGAAAAUAAAGAGACAAUUCAGAACAGUUUACGACAAGUUUGGCAAAACAGAUUCAACUACCUUGAAAAAGCUAGAGAGAGAAAAGCUCUGUUUCUAAAAGAAAAAUCCCAAAAGGCUUCAGAGCGUUUAUUAGUUCAAAACUUAAAUAAUGAGCGCACUCUUUUGACCAGAGGACUACUUAAAAUUGACAGACUGGAGAAGAAUGAGGCUGUCCUAAAAGAGAAAAGCCUGAUUGUUAAGCAAAAACUAAAAGCAGAAAAAUAUAGAAAGAAUUUACUUAAAGAAAUGAAAAAAGUUAGAUCUCAAGAAAUAUAUAAAAGACAUUGUGAAGAAAAAUUUGUUAUGGAUAUGAUUGCCUUUGAAAAAGCCUGUGAAAGACUUCAAGAUGCUAAAACAAAAGUAGCAAUUGUGAAAACAAAUUUAGACUUUAAAGUUCCCAAUGGACUGAUAAAAUGAAUCAAUGCCAGAUCACAUCCUAUGAUCAUCUUAAAUUAUAGUCAUUAUUUUUAGUUGAAGGAAUUUGAAAUAAUACUCUAAAGCAAGAAAUACUCUACAUCACAAGAUGGAUUUAUAUAUAAGUCUUCUAAAAAUAUAAAGAUUAGUUAAAAUGUUUCUCUUAUUGGUCAUAAUUUAACUUAAAGUUGACUUAGCACCUCUGAAAAAUUUCUUAGAUCAGAUGCCUAAGGAACAAUUAAACUGAUUUAAUGUAUUGCAGACAAUGUUGCAAUGACAUUGCUGAUAUUCUGUUUCAUAUUCUUUCUAAAUAUAGCAAUUCAUAAGCUAAUUUAGGUUUUUCUGGAAACCUUAGAAUAGUAAUUUCUACUCCAACUGCUGACUUUUAUUAAGACACUGUGUACGUUGAUGACUUUUAUUACCUGCUUUUAUAUAUUUCCUGCUUAUUUUGUUAAAACAAUUUCUGAAUUUAUUUUUUAAAGUAUGGUUUCAAUAUUUUGUCAGUGAUAUAUGCUGUUAUAAAAAUUCAGAAAAUAUGAACUAUGAAAAGUAAAUUAAACAUUCUUAUCACCUUC